CUCCCCAGAGACGCUCAUCCUACAGCCUCAGCUCGGGCCCAGCCUUCUCUCUCCAGCUGCCACCACAGCCUGGAGGCGCCUGCCUCCACCCUCCCGAAUGGUGCUCCUCCUAGCAGGCCUCGGUCCAGGAUCCAAGCCCCCUUUGCCCCCUGCCUUGGAGCUGUUGCUCCGGGUUUGUCACAGUGGACUCCCUGUGGCGGGAAGGGAAGAACUUUUGCACAGACAAGGCUUCAGCUCUAGGAACCCCACUGACAACUUGAAUCUCAACCUCUAACCUAGUGUGAGGUUCUUCCUGUGCCCACCUUUUCUGCCUUUUGAGAAGAGAAACUCUUCUCCUGGCCAUCUAGAGCCCAGGAAGCCCCAAGCUGGGGCCCUGGUCCCAGCAUGUCAGUCCUCUCUUGUGCAUAGGGCUCUGCCCUCCCCCUGUCAGCAUGGCUGAGCUCAGACAGGUUCCAGGAGGGCGGGAGACCCCACAGGGGGAGCUGCGGCCUGAAGUUGUAGAGGAUGAAGUCCCUAGGAGCCCAGUCGCAGAAGAGCCUGGAGGAGGUGGAAGCAGCAGCAGUGAGGCCAAAUUGUCCCCAAGAGAGGAGGAAGAACUGGAUCCUAGAAUACAGCUGAGUGCCAGGAGUCCCUGGUGAAGCAGGCCAAAUGGAAUGUGUUGCUGACUGCCCAAAACUGUCCCAGGUCCUCAGUGGAUUCCUGCUCAGCCUUUCCCUGGGUGUCGCCUAGUAGUAACAACUUAUGCUGAGCCAUCCAAUCCAUUGAUGAUCUUGUCAGGAGCUGGAAGUUGAUGACUGGAAGCAUUUGAGGCCAUGGAAUCCAGUGGGGAUCCCGUCUUGGACUUUGAUUUGCCACAUGAACAUUGCAGGGUGGCCUUUACCAACUGACCCCCCACAAUCAAUGUUUGUUGCAUUUCCAAUCCCUGUCCUUUUCCUACGUGGGCUGUGGUUUUCCUAGAUUACAGCACUUCUUUCUUUACUGAGAUGUCCUUCCAGUGGUGUCCUCAUUCCCAGGAGGGUGGUCACAGUGGAAGGAAAGUGAGAUCAAAGGUCGGUCCUGGAUCCAGACCCAAGUCUGUCACUAAUUUUCCGCCUGGUUGUUUCUCAUCUAUCAAAUGCAAAGUUGCUGAGAAAGAAUAUUCCAGCAGGAGGUGCUGAAAGAACUGGUCACUCGUCUCCCAGAUAGCCUAAAAGCCCCUGUAGGCCUCGUCAAGCCCCAGGAAGCUGGGCCCCCAGGGAGGAGGAGUUGGAGCACCUGAACCAGGCCAGCGAGGAGAUCAACCAGGUGGAACUACAGCUGGAUGAGGCCAGGACCACCUAUCGGAGGAUCCUACAGGAGUCGGCGAGGAAACUGAAUACACAGGGUUCCCACUUGGGGAGCUGCAUCGAGAAAGCCCGGCCCUACUAUGAGGCUCGGCGGCUGGCUAAGGAGGGGAAAAGGCUAGCAGCCUUUGGGAGUGCUGGAUUUCACACAUCUACCCUCCACUGGCAAAAUUUUUAUUUCUUCUAGUCCAUAUCCUUAUGAAAUAUUCUUUAUAGAAUGUUGCUUCCUUGGCAUUUAUCCUCAGCACAGUUUGGGAAAUGAAGCCGACAUUGCUAGCUCAGCAGGAGACACAGAAGGCAGCGCUGCGGUACGAGCGGGCCGUAAGCAUGCACAACGCUGCUCGAGAAAUGGUGUUUGUGGCUGAGCAGGGCGUCAUGGCUGACAAGAACCGACUGGACCCCACGUGGCAGGAGAUGCUGAACCAUGCUACCUGCAAGGUGAAUGAGGCGGAGGAAGAGCGGCUUCGAGGUGAGCGGGAGCACCAGCGAGUGACUCGGCUGUGCCAACAGGCUGAGGCUCGGGUCCAAGCCCUGCAGAAGACCCUCCGGAGGGCCAUCGGCAAGAGCCGCCCCUACUUUGAGCUCAAGGCCCAGUUCAGCCAGAUCCUGGAGGAGCACAAGGCCAAGGUGACAGAACUGGAGCAGCAGGUAGCUCAGGCCAAGACGCGCUACUCCGUGGCCCUUCGUAACCUGGAGCAGAUCAGCGAGCAGAUUCACGCACGGCGCCGCGGGGGUCUGCCUCCCCACCCCCUGGGCCCUCGGCGCUCCUCCCCCGUGGGGGCCGAGGCAGGACCCGAGGACAUGGAGGACGGAGACAGCGGGAUUGAGGGGGCCGAGGGUGCGGGGCUGGAGGAGGGCAGCAGCCUGGGGCCCGGCCCCGCCCCCGACACCGAUACCCUGAGUCUGCUGAGCCUGCGCACGGUGGCUUCAGACCUGCAGAAGUGCGACUCCGUGGAGCACUUGCGAGGCCUCUCGGACCACGUCAGUCUGGACGGCCAAGAGCUGGGAACGCGGAGUGGAGGGCGCCGGGGCAGCGACGGCGGAGCCCGUGGGGGUCGGCACCAGCGCAGCGUCAGCCUGUAGCCGAGGGGCCAGGGUUCCUGGCUUGAAUCUGCCACCACGGGCCGGUUGGGGCCCACAGUCUUCUCACGCCCUCUCCUCUGGGGCCUCGUCUUCCCGAAGGUCCCCUUCUCCAGUGCUUCCCUGGGAGAGGCCAGCUGUGUUCGAGUCCUCUGUGCCUGCCCUGGCGUUCUCACAGCCUCCCCCUUCCCCUCAGCAGGCGGCUCUCUUUGCCUUACCCAUUCAGAAGGCUCGCCCUCGGCGCUCUGUCUGCCUCUGCCUGCCAGCUCAUCACGAUCUGCAGGGCAUUGACCCUUUGCUUUCCCUUUCUGCUCCCUCUCUUUCCAUCUGUUUGGCUUUUUCCCUCAGGGAACUUGGUCUAGAAGGCACUGGGAAGCUCAUCAGAGAAAAUGGGUGCUGGGCCUGAGUACUCCCGUCGGAGGGGAUGGACAGUCACCCCUCCCGUUGGUUUCCAGCCCCGCCCCCCUUCCCAAGGCAACUCUGGAGGGUACCCUAGGUAUGCUGCUGAGCCCUGCCCCCCGUCCUGCUCCAGCCUGCCCGUGUGUAACCUGUAAGAUGUACUGUGUGCCUCCGGAAGACACCACCUUUCCCUUCAGCAUUCCCUUUCAUGACCUGAGGCACUCUGCGAUGUGUGCCCCAAAGCAGAACUUACAGGGCCUGCAGGAAGCUGGUGUCAGGGAGAGAAACCCAACCCCACUGUCAACAUAGGGAGCAUCACCAACUCCAGACUGGCUCCUGUGGGUAUGGUGUUUCCGCUGGGCUGGGUCCUCAACAUUGCCAAGGUGCUAGUGGGUCCCUAAGAGGGCCCAUGUUGGGGGUGAAGUCAUGAGGUCCUGAAGGCUUAGGCCCCUGUCAUUCCCACCCUCACUCUUGCUGCACAGUUGUGUUUACUUUUUCUGGGUAGAGGAUGCUGAACUGACUCAGCACCCUCCUGCAGGACGGGGUUAGGGAAUUUGGUGCUCAAUUGCUCUCCCUUGCUCUUCCCCAAACUGAAAAUACCUACUGCAGGAUCCCUCGGGGCACACUGAAGCUUGGCUGCCAACCCUCUUACUUCCUUUGUUACAGGGAGGGGUUGGCUUGGGGUGAAAAGUUCUGCCCUCCGCAGGGAGCAGCUCCAGCUGCCUGGCAGUGCUCCCAGUUUGUAGGGAAGCCACACCAGAUCUGGGUGCCUUGGGAGAACCAGUCCUUCCUUUUGACCCACCCCAGGAAGAUGGAGUGCUCUUUUCUAGGCCCAUGUUCUGCCAGCAACCGGGAUGCGUGGGCAACUGGACUCUGCACGGGGGUCUACAGGUUGAGGGAGGUUGGUCACAAUGAGAACCUCGGGGUUUGAGGUGGCCAUGGGCAGACAGCCGAAAGGGAGGGAGGGUGUGGGUGUGCGUGUGUGCAUGUGCUGGUGUGUAAGGGGGAAAGGGUCUUUCCUGGUUUUAUUUAAAUAAAGUAGUUUAUGUAACAGUUAA